GCUUACCUACUGCCUUCUCCGACCGUCCGUCCUCGGGGCAGGCGUGCUCUCUUCCCUGAGCUUUUAGGGGUUGGCUUUUCCAGUUCCAGAUCAGCUACAGCAAACAUCGUUCGAGAUGUCCCACCAAGAGGGCAGCACAGGUGGCUUACCAGACUUAGUGACUGAAAGCCUGUUCAGCAGCCCAGAGGAGCAGUCUGGAGUAGCAGCGGUGACGGCGGCCUCCUCAGACAUUGAAAUGGCAGCCACAGAGCCAUCGACCGGAGAUGGUGGUGAUACCAGGGAUGGUGGUUUCCUGAACGAUGCCAGCACAGAAAAUCAAAACACAGACUCAGAAAGUUCAAGUGAAGACGUCGAACUUGAAAGCAUGGGUGAAGGUUUAUUUGGUUACCCGUUAGUGGGAGAGGAGACAGAAAGGGAGGAGGAAGAAGAAGAGAUGGAGGAGGAAGGGGAGGAGGAAGAACAGCCUCGGAUGUGUCCACGAUGCGGUGGCACCAACCAUGAUCAGUGUUUGUUAGACGAGGAUCAGGCGUUGGAGGAGUGGAUUUCCUCAGAGACAUCUGCCCUGCCCCGAUCUCGCUGGCAAGUCCUUACUGCUCUUCGCCAGCGGCAGCUGGGUUCAAGUGCCCGCUUUGUAUAUGAGGCCUGUGGGGCAAGAACCUUUGUGCAGCGUUUCCGCCUGCAGUAUCUUCUUGGAAGCCAUGCCGGUUCUGUCAGUACCAUACACUUUAACCAGCGUGGCACCCGACUGGCCAGUAGCGGUGAUGACUUAAGGGUGAUAGUGUGGGACUGGGUGCGGCAGAAGCCAGUACUGAACUUUGAGAGUGGUCACGAUAUUAAUGUCAUCCAGGCUAAGUUCUUUCCUAACUGUGGUGAUUCCACUCUGGCCAUGUGUGGCCAUGAUGGACAGGUACGGGUAGCAGAACUAAUUAAUGCAUCAUAUUGCGAGAAUACUAAGCGUGUGGCCAAGCACAGGGGACCUGCCCACGAGUUGGCUCUGGAGCCAGACUCUCCUUAUAAGUUCCUCACUUCAGGUGAAGAUGCCGUUGUGUUCACCAUUGACCUCAGGCAAGACCGGCCAGCUUCAAAAGUUGUGGUAACAAGAGAAAAUGAUAAGAAAGUCGGACUGUAUACAAUCUCUAUGAAUCCUGCCAAUAUUUACCAAUUUGCAGUGGGUGGACAUGAUCAGUUUGUAAGGAUUUAUGACCAGAGGAGAAUUGAUAAGAAAGAAAACAAUGGAGUACUCAAGAAAUUCACUCCUCAUCAUCUGGUUUAUUGUGAUUUCCCAACAAACAUCACCUGCGUUGUGUACAGCCACGAUGGCACAGAGCUCCUGGCCAGCUACAAUGAUGAAGAUAUUUACCUCUUCAACUCCUCUCUCAGUGAUGGUGCUCAAUAUGUUAAGAGAUAUAAGGGGCACAGAAAUAAUGACACAAUCAAAUGUGUUAAUUUCUAUGGCCCCCGGAGUGAGUUUGUCGUGAGCGGUAGUGAUUGUGGGCACGUCUUCUUCUGGGAGAAAUCAUCCUCCCAGAUCAUCCAGUUCAUGGAGGGGGACAGAGGAGAUAUAGUAAACUGUCUUGAACCCCACCCUUACCUACCUGUGUUGGCGACCAGUGGCCUAGAUCAGCAUGUCAGGAUCUGGACACCCACAGCUAAAACUGCCACUGAGCUUACUGGGUUAAAAGAUGUGAUUAAGAAGAACAAGCAGGAGCGAGAUGAAGACAACUUGAACUAUACGGACUCGUUUGACAACCGCAUGCUUCGGUUCUUCGUGCGUCACCUGUUACAGAGAGCUCAUCAACCCGGCUGGAGAGAUCAUGGAGCUGAGUUCCCAGAUGAAGAAGAGUUGGAUGAGUCUUCCAGCACCUCAGAUACAUCCGAGGAGGAGGGCCAAGAUCGAGUGCAGUGCAUACCAUCCUGAAGGCCUCAUAUCCAGUCCAGCUAGAUGCCACCUAAGUACACUGGACUUUAAAAUUCAGUUUGACUAAUUUAGAAUUGUCAAUUGAUUAACAGAUUUGCUUUUUGUCUUCUGUUUUUGUUACCCCUUAUAUGAGUGCAUACACAACUUAUUUAUGCCUCUUUUCCUUUGUUCCCUUAUAAUUGACCUCUAAAAUUGCAUAAUUUUGUUGAAAAAAUUAAUGGCCUUAUUAGAUGUAUCUACUCAUUUCAGACAUUCUGAAAGCUAUUACUUUUUAGUUUUUUCAUUUUUUACCAAUUUAUUUUGAAGAUAAAGUUCUUCAGUUGAGUUGAAAAUUUCAUAAACGUGUUUAUUCUUUAGAGGUAAAAUAAGGCAAACCAUAGUUCUUUGAAUACUGACACACACAUACACACAGUCUCAGAAAAGGAAAAGAGAAGUAGUGUGUAGAUUAAUUCCUAACACUUGGCCACACACACACACAGCUUCAAAAGUUGUAGUAACAAGAGAGAAGAAUAAGAAAGUGGGACUGUAUACAAUCUCUAUGAAUCCUGCCAAUAUUUACCAAUUCGCAGUGGGUGGACAUGAUCGGUUUUUAAGGAUUUAUGACCAGAGGAGAAUUGAUGAGAAAGAAAACAAUGGAGUACUCAAGAAAUUCACUCUUCAUCAUCUGGUUAAUUGUGAUUUUCCAACAAACAUCACCUGCAUUGUGUACAGCCACGAUGGCACAGAGCUCCUGGCCAGCUAUGCACACACACAUACACACAGAGCCUUAGAAAAGGAAAACAAGAAGUAGUGUGUAGAUGAAUUCCUAACCAGAUAAUUCAUCUCCUCAGAGCAAAUAACUUGGGAUUAUCCACAUUUUCUGAAUCAAUAUGUUAAUAAUAUUGAUUAAUUUGAGCACACUGAAGCUGGUAAGAACUAAAUUAAAUUUAAUCACAUGACAUUGUUUACUCUAUGCAUUAAAUGUUCUUGAAGUUUUAUGGUUGGGAACUCCCACAGGAUUACAUUCCAGGAAGUCCUCCUGGCGCAAGCAUCUCCUAUAAGAUACCAGAUAGGAAUAUAAAAAUCUCUCAUAUUUGAAAACAUUUAUUUUAAUUAACUUUUAAGAAUAAGUUGCAAUAAAAAUUGUUUAUACUUACACAUAACCAUUUGAUACAGUUGGUAGAAAAAUCCUAUUUAACAUCCAUGCAUUGCUUAAAAUUUAGCUGUUUUAUGAGUUUGUUUUGAAAAUUGUUGCAAUAAAAAUUGUUUAUACUUACAAGUGAUGUAGUUGGUAGAAAAAUCCUAUUUGACAUCCAUGCAUUGCUUAAAAUUUAGCUGUUUUAUGAGUUUGUUUUAAAAAUUGUUGCAGUAAAAAUUGUUUAUACUUACAAGUGAUGUAGUUGGUAGAAAAAUCCUAUUUGACAUCCAUGGAUUGCUUAAAGUUCUCUCAGCUGUCCUCGAGUUUAAAUUGUUUUAAAAAUUGUCUUAAGCUUUACUUAAUAUAAAUUUAAGUUACUAGAUGUUAAAUUACUGUUCAAUAAAAAUAUUCAUUUUUAUUUUA